AUGAUGGGCUCUCCUAAGUGAGGCCAUGGACAGCCAGGAUGUGCGUCUCGGCACCGGGGUGAGUCUUUCUUGGCCCGCUGGCAGAACCCUGGGUCAGAUGGGAGGGUUGUUGGUGCCCGGCUGUGUGUCUGCCAGCCCCUUCAUCCCUAUCCUGGCUGCUGUGUAGCUCCUGCCUCCCCAUAACUCUUGGGGGGCUGCCCGGGUCCACACUGGCCCCGUGGGGAUGGCAGUAGGCAGAGAGGGGCGGUCCUGACCCCAGAGAAAUCCCAUGGGUGAGUAGGACUUGUAGGAGAUGGCAGUUCCCUCCCUGGAGCAUGUGUCCCCAAGACUUAGAGGUCGUGGUGGGGCAGGAAGCAGGUAGUCAGGGUGGGCUUUUGGGAGGAGAUGGCAUCACAGUACGGAGGGAGUCAUGCACGAGGCACCAGGAAGGGGCAAGCCGGGUGAGGACAGGCUCCUCCUGGGGACCCAGGACCUGACGGAACGGCAUCACUCUUAAUGGCACCGUCGCGAGCCUCUUCUGGGCCAGCAGCCGGAGCUCACCCAGGGCACAUCCUUAAACCUCAGGGUCCCCUGGUGGCAGCUGCCAUGGUCGUCCUGUUUCCCAGGGAGGGAAGCUGGUGUCUGAGGCUGGCACUCUGCUAGGUAGCACAGUUGGGGAGUGGCAGUGCUGGGAUGGAAGACAGACAAGCUGGCACCUGCACAUCUGCACGUCCUGUCGUUGAGGUGACCUCUAGCCAGCCAGCUCAUCUGCUCCUUUGCAGAUGAGGCCAGAGAGACGGGAGUCUCUGGUGUGGAGGGGAGGGCACUGGGUUUGGUGGGCUGGCCCUGGGGUAACUUGCCUGCCUGUGCUUCAGUGUCCCCCUCUGUAAACAGGGUGUGACGUCCCCCCGGCCAUGUCGGAGGCUCCGAGAGGGCAGCGGGUCCAUCUCAGCAGAUGCUCUGCUGACGGAUGCUGCUGGCUGGCCCCUGCUCCCACCCUCCCCUCCUUUGGUAGCCUCCCUGGGCCGGGCUGUUCCCACGGCUGCCCAGCCACAGGAAGCCAUCUGGAGGCCUUGUUUACCCCUCCCCCUGGCCUCCCUGGCAGGAAGUCACCGGAAGGGCCGUCCCGAGGGGCCCCGGGCCUGUGAGGACAGCCAUCGGCUCAGAGGUCUGUGCUGUGGAGUCCCAGGAUAGCAUGCGGGGGCAGGGAGCUCAGAGAACAGCAGGUGGAGCGGGGCUCCAAGGCACUGGAGCACGUGGGCCGGAGCAUGGACAGAACCAUUUACCGAGCGCAUCCAUCUGUCCAUCCACACAGUCACCUACCCCUCCCCCGCUGUGGCCCCAGCAGGGCCCAGUCCCAUGAAGCUCACAGUCUCAAGGCAUGGACGAGGCCACUCCAGCUUCAGCCCAGGGGGGCCCCGUGAUGCCAGGGCCAUUCCUCCAGCUCCCGGGAUCCCACACCUCCCCUGAUAUCACACAAGCCACCCUGGGUCGGGGCUGGAGGAGGAGACCUGGGCAGCAGCUGGGGUGUCCAGGAGAAGGGAGUUGGGGAGAGGGGUGCCAGCAGAGGGUGCAGCCUCUAGAAACAUUGGAGGCCGCCCUGGGUGACGGGUCUGAGGCUGCAAGGUGUGGGUGGAGCAGGUGAAGGGAGAGGUGGGCAGGCACAGCUGGCAGGGGCUGAAGGCAUGGAUGGGACCAGUCGGGGUACUUGUGGCCCUGCAGAACCCCUCUCUCCACCACCUCCUCCAGCCCUCUGGCGCCCUGCUCAGGGAGGGCUCCCCCAGAUAACCCUGUAGGUCUGGACCCUCCUGGAGUGGGCUCAGGGGCCUGGGUUUCCACUCCACAGGAUGGGUCCAGCUGCCCCGGCAUUUGUGGCAGCCCCAGUGCCCACUGACAGGCCUGAGUGUAGCUGGCUAGGCCCAGGGCCUUUCCCACAGACACUGCCAGCAGGGACUACCUGGCCCUAGGGGGAUCUUUGACCUCCGUGGGGCCUUGCGCCCUGUGUUCUUGGCGGCCUCGCGCCUGUCCCGGCCUCCUGCCUUCGGGAGCUGGGUGGAGUGGGGGCAGGCAGCCCUGCCCCCGCCCACAUGGGGAGGCUGAGGAUUGGCCCUUCCGCCUCUGGCUACCCCUCUUCCCCUCCCCCAUACCUCCUGCUCCCCUUUUUCCUCACUUUCCCCCCACCCCUCCCCCCUGCUUCCGCUUUCUCAUCCCUUUAGAAGGUGCCUACUCAUGAUCGUCUUGAGUAAAGCCCUCCCUGAGAGUGUCUUGGGGUUUCGGGCCUGGCAAGCAUCCCCAGCCUCCCCUGAAGAGGAAGUGAGCGUGAGAACCGGGCCUUUGGCGGAUCCAGGUGCCUGCGGGCAGCCCGGGGGCUUGUUUGUUGGGUGCCUGGCCAGCGGGCCGGUCCAGAGCAGGAAUAGAUGUCUCAGGAGGGUCCCUGGCUGGUCCCAAGCACCUCCUGUGUGCACCAGGGCCGCUGUUCUUCCGUCCAGCCUCCCAGCAGCCCUGGGGUGUGGGUGCCUCUGAUUCGGAGGGAGUGACGGGACUUAGGGUUAGCCAGCUCCCCAGGUCAGAGACGCAGAGCCCUGGGCCAACCCCAGGAUGAGCCCCAUCAGCCUCUCCUUCCUGACUCAUUCAAGAUAGUAAGUGAAAGAGGGCAUGCAACCAGCACGCAGCCCCAGAGGAAGGCUGCAGCGGCCUCGCGCGGGGCCAAGGAGGCUGGGCACCGUGUGUGCCGUGGCACUGCCCUCCCUGGUGUUGCUGAUGCUGCUGAGAUGGGAGAAUGUUGUGGGAUUCUGGGGGAGGCUCUGGUCUGAGAGUCCCGAGCCUGGGGAGAUGGCCUGGCUGGGCCCAGGCUGGCCACAGGGGCACCCCAGACUUUUUUCCUGGGCAUGGUGUACAGUAAGUCCUCACAUCACAUCAUCCAUAAGUUCUUGGAAGCUGCGGCUUUAAGCAAAACGAUGCCAGUUUUAAGUGAAAAUUGGUUUAAGGACACUAGUGUUCCCAUAAGUUGAUAGAGAUAGAUAAGAGUUAAGUUCCUGCCAGGUAUUUCUGGUCACAAAAACGUCACCAGGCUUCCAAUGAAGACCCCAAACACUUCUAACAUUAAACACUGAAGUAAAUGUGAGCUACACAUACAUGUAAGAAAAGUGAAUUAAACAGGGAAGAGAAUUGCUUCCCCAGCUUUCCGUGGGCCAGUGAGUGGUAACGGAACACACAUCUCACGGCAACCAUGGUCGGGAGCUCCUCCUGCCACCACGCACUUCAAAAUCAAACGAUCACAAACGUGGCGGCUUCCUGUAUUGCCACGCAUUCGUCUGACUAUGUCUAUUUGACGAAUUUUUAUUUUGCAAUAAUUUUUAUUCAUUUAUUCAUUCAUUUUCCAACCCACUAAUUCCAGUGCAGGGUCAUGAGUGGCUGAGCCUGUCUCAGCAGCUCUGGGCACAAGGUGGGACCUGACUCUGCUCAGGACACCAUCCCCUCUCGGGGCACACUCCCAUGCACAGCCACACCCACUCAGCCAGGGCCACGGCGACACGCCUGUUCACCGGAUGUGCACAGCACUGGGGUAUGGGGGAGCCGGAGGACAGGGAGAAAACCCACACAGACCUGGGGAGCUCGUGCACAUGCCACGCAAUGGCCCUGAAAGGGAAGCGAUUUUUUUUUCUCGUCAGCGUUAUCACAAAACCACGUUGAAAGCAACAGUGUUAUUUGAGGAGCUGCUGUACUUGACGGAUGGUGCAGGACAAGGUGGGCCCUCUUCGGGGCCUCUGCGCCUCUCCCCCUUUCAGGGGGUUGGGGUAGAAACUGGAUCAAGGAUAGGGGACUCUCAUAGGAUUGGAGGGUCCAUUGGGGCAGGGCCCCCCAGCAGCUGAGGGCCUCUCUCCCCCUGUCCUGGGGUCCUGGGGUCUCUGGCCCCCAUGAGUCCAGCUCCUGAUUGCUCUGCCAAGUUUGCUGUCAUGCCAGGAACUAAGCCUUUCUCCUCGUGAGCUCUCUUGCACCCACAGUAUAGCCAUGGUAUUCAGUAGGUGCCCAGUAAGUGUGGGCUGGUGAAUGGGCCUCCAGGGAGGUGGGAUUUGGAUGGACAGAAUGGACGGGUCCUUGGGAGGUGGUACUGAGUCAGCAGAGGCUUGGGGGCAGAGCAUCUCUGCAGAGGCAGGGGCUCCAUCCUCAAGGACCCCCUGAGGGCCUCCAGGAGGAGGCAGCCAUGGGGUGCGUGGGGAAGUAGGAGUGGCAGCUCUGAGUCAGCUUGUCCCAGCUCUGAGCUCCCUCCCGCACCUACCUGUCUCCACUGUGGGGGCCACACAGCCUUUACAUAUAAAGGGCAUGGAGCAGCGCCUGGCACUCAGGCUGCCAGUACCACCAACUGGCAGCACUCAUUGGGCACUGACUGUCUACAUUGCCAGGAGUGUUCAAGAAGUAAUUUAAACUGCCAGAAAUCCUCAUCCCACGGCAUUAACUGACACCUGCUUUGGGCCUGACCCUGUGCCUGAUCCUGGGGACCUGGCAUGGGUCAGUCAACGCUCCCUGUCUGCCGCCCACAGUCCAUGACAGGGACAGACAAGUCACGAACAGGGCUGCAGGGGCUGACCCAGGAAUGAGCAGGACCUCUCUGGGACUGUUUAGGGCUUUGGCCCCCUGGUGAGGGAGCAGCGAGGCUGUGGGGACCCAGGUCCCUUGGGCCUUGCAUGCCUGGCUCCUGAUCCUGUGGGCCCCAUGCAGAAGUGGCCCCCAGUUCUUUCUGGGUGCUUGGCAUGUCCAGUCUUCCUUGGGGGCUCCCCAGGCAAUUUUGGCUAGACACCCAGCAGACGCUCCUUCCUCCAGGCCCCCCAACCUCCGGGUCCCUGAGGUCGGAGCCAGUUUUCCCCAAGACCACCCAAGCAGUGACUUUGGGUCCACCCACAGAUGCCCUGGUCACUGUGUUGCUGGGAGUGCUUGGGUGAGAAGGAAUGGCUGCGGGCGGGUCUUCCUUUCUUCAUCCUCAGCAUCCUCAUCCAUCACUGAGGAUGCUUGUCUCUGCCUUACUCCCACUCACAGGACAGUCGAAUAUGUUCACACAUCCACUGAGCCAGCACCUGCUGUGUACGGUGCCCAUUGAGAACCAGGGAGCCGAGGGUGGAGCUGUGGCCGGUCUCUUGUCCUGCGUGGGGAGAGAGGCUGACAAGCUUUGCCAGAAGGGGGACAGAUGAUCCCUACUGUGUGUGGGGGACAGAGGACAGGUCUCGGUGGCUAGCAGGAGGAACAGGAGGAUGCUGAACCUGAGAUCCGAGUGGUAAGAAGGGGCCAGCACCGGACGAUGUGGGGACAGAGCAUGCUCCUGGCCUCCAGCACAGGCAGUGCAAGGGCUCGGAGGCAGGACUGUGCUUGGCAAGUUGCAGGAACAGCUGGGAGGCAGGUGAGGCUACAGCAGAUGAGGAGAGGGGAGUGGUAGGAGGUCAGAGGGCAGGGAGCAGCUCGCGUGGGGCCUUUAGGGCGAUAAGGAUUUUUGGCUUUCCUGAGUGACGCGGGCACCACUGGAGGCUUUGAGCGGAGGGGGCUAUGAUCUGACUUAGGUCGAGGACACUGGUGGGGGCAGUGGUGGGGAUACCCAGGAUGCCAGAUGGGUAUCCCAGAUUCUUGGUGACCCUCGGUAGCCCCUCUGGGCGGUGGCUUUAGGCAUCUGGGCUCAGGUGUCACCAUUUCACUUGUCGGCCACCCACGGCUGCUUCCUGCCCCAUCUGGGGAUUCCGGGGACUUUCCAUUUCCUCACCUUGCACUUGAUUCUGUGAUGUGCCUGGACUGGGGAUUGUGGAGGCCUGUCCGUGCCCUGAAGCACUUCUGAGAAGCCGGGGAGCAGUUCCCUGGGGUUUCCCCUGGGAAGUCCUGCCGUCCUCUUUCUGCUGCCACCCAGAGCCCGCCCUUUCCGGAGAGCAGUUCCCUGGGGUGUCCCCCUGGGAAGUCCUGCCCUCCUGCCUCUGGCCCUUGCUCAAGCCGCGCCCCCAUCUGGAUGCCCACUUCUUCCACUCUGCUCUGUUGGACCAAUUAGGCCAACUCUGGGGAUAUGUGACCCCAGUGUUUGUGAUCAAACGGGGCCCAGACUCAUUGACAUCCUGCGUGAACUACAGUUUUGGUAGAGGUGCAAGUGGAUUCUGUGUGGCACAGAAGAUGGCGAGUGGUGACGGCUGUGUUGCCUGCAUGCCACCGACAGCCCGCCUCUUCUUUCCAUCUUAAUCCAUCUUGCCAGCUCUCAAGGGCUGUAGGCACUUCGCCCUGAAUCCUCCUCUGAGCCGGCUUUGCCUCCUGCUGUUCCCACUGAGCGAAUUAAAUAAGUCUUUGCCCUGUGCCCACUGUAUGUGCAAGGUCAUGCAGGUUAUGCUUUGAACUUCCAAAAAUGCGCUCAGAAAUCUUUCCUGUCCUCUAGGGCCCAUCUCUGAUGCCACCUUCACCUUCUGGAUUCUCUCCAGGGGAGGAGGUCAGGCCCUUGGGAGGUACCCUUUGCCCUCUCUGCUGGGGAUCCUGGAGAGUCCCUCCCCAACUCCCCUGGCCACUGGGACCUCUCUUCCUCCCUGACCUGCCCAGCAUCCUCCCUUGGCAGCCUGGCACAGCCCGGACAGAACCUAGAAGGUGUGGAUUCUGCCUGCCUGCCCUGUGUCCCCACAGUCCACAUGCUGGCCUGGACUCUCAGGCCUCCCCACCUCCAGUCCCUCUCCUGCCCUCUCCAUUCCUUCACACACGUGGGCACAAAGCUGGGGCUUCUGUAAGGGUGCAUCUGGUAGGACCUCAACCUCCCGUACCCAAUGGGGUCUUGGGAGAACAGAAGUUGUGGGUGAUGGUUAAGGUGUAGCCCUCUUCCCAACCUUGCACAGCCCCCUGGCUCAGUCCCUGAGGGUAAAAUUCAGACAGAGCUGGAAAUGACCCAAAUGUCCAUCAGCUGAGGAUAAACGAAAUGUGGCAGGCCCACAGAGUAGAACAAGCUUGCCCAGCCAGCAGCGCGGCCCAGGACGGCUUUGAAUGUGGCCCAACACACAUUCAUAAACUUUCUAUUUUUUUUUUUUUUUUGAGAUGGAGUCUCACUCUGUUGCCCAGGCUGGAGUGCAGUGGUGGGAUCUUGGCUCACUGCAACCUCCACCUCCUGGGUUUAAGUGAUUCUCCUGCUUCAGCCUCCCAAGUAGAUGGGAUUACAGGUGCCCGCCACCACACCCAGCUAAUUUUUGUAUUUUUAGUAGAGAUGGGGUUUUGCCAUGUUGGCCAGGCUGGUUUCAAACUCCUGACCUCAAGUGAUCCACCUGCCUCAGCCUCCCAAAGUGGUAAGAUGACAGGCGUGAGCCACCGUGCCUGGCCAAAUUUGUAAACUUUCUUAAAACAUCAUGAGGUUUUUUGUUGUUGUUGUUGUUCAUCAGCCAUCAUUAGCGUUAGUGUAUUUUAUGUGUGGUCCUAAACAAUUCUUCCAGCGUGGCCCAGGGAAGCCAAAAGAUUGCACACUCCUGCAGUAGAAUAUAGGCGGCCAACAGGUGGAGCGGGCACAGACUCAGGCUGCGCCGUGGCUGAGCCUUUACGACGCCAGGAGAAGCGAAAGGAACCAGGCGCAGAGGGCCACGUGGUGUGUGAGGCCAUUCACAGCAAAUGUCCUGAACAGGCAAGUCCACAGAGACAGAAAGCAGACUUGUGGUUGCCAGGGGCUGGGGGAGGAGGGGUGGAGUGACUGCUGGUGGGAGGGGGCGAUGGAAGUGUUCUGGAAUUAGUGGUGAUGAUUACACAGCACUGUGAAUAUAUUAAAAACACUGAAGGUUACACUUUAAGAUGGCUAAAAUGACUGGGCCUGGUGGCUCACGCCUGUAAUCCCAGCACUUUGGGAGGCCAAGGUGGGCGGAUCACCUGAGGUCAGGAGUUUGGGACCAGCCUGGCCAACAUGGCGAAACCCUGUCUCUACUAAAAAUACAAAAAUUAGCCGGUUGUGGUCAUGGGCGCCCGUAAUUCCAGCUACUUGGGAGGCUGAGGCAGGAGAAUUGCUUGAACCCGGGGGCGGAGGUUGCAGUGAGCUGAGGUCGUGCCACUGCACUCCAGCCUGGGUAACAGAGCGAGACUCUGUCUGAAAAAAAAAAAAAAGACUAAAAUGGUGGAUUUCAUGUGUUAUGAAUUUUAUCUCAAAAAAUAAAUUAGGAUAGCACCCCCGCCUACACAGACUCUGUCCUGAGCAGCUCUCAGAAGUCCGUAAAAUAGGGUGAAAGUGUCGUUGCCCUGCCCCCGGGUUCCCAGUGCUGUGGGGACGUCACCAGCUGCUGGGGAACAGAGGGAUGCUGGCACCCACCCAGGGCUCAGGGCAGGGCAGGAGCUUGGUGUGCGCUAGAGACUAGAGUGAGAAGGCCCUUCCCCGGCCCUCACAGAGUGCCUUGCCACUGGGGAGUUGAGUGAAGGCACAGACAAGGUUGUGAGGUACCCACGCUGCCGUGUAGUGUCACCACGCCCUGAUGUGUAUAACCUGUUUUCUUUGCUCAUCUGGGUGGACUGGUGGGGCAUUUGAUUCUGGAGGGUGGGGUUCCAGUCUGCAUGGUUCCCUGGGGAUCCCUGGCCCCAACAUGAAGGCAGUGUGGCCUGAGGGCCUCUCAGUCCCCAAGGUGCUGACCCACCGCUGCCUUUCCCGAGUCCUCCCUGGGCCCUGCUAGGGGAGGCCUGGGAGCUGCAGCAUCCAACAGGCCCGUGUGAAUGGCCUGGCCACAGCACUGCCAGACAGGGCAAAGUUCCUGGCCCGGGGCUGUCUCUGAGCCCUGGAGCUGGCGGGGUAGGGAUCAGCUCCUGUGAGCUCCCUCCAUCCCCAGAUCCACCCUUCAGGUCCAGGGCUAUUUGGUGGCAGCUCCUGGUGGGGCAGGGGGAUGGGAGGGAUGGGAGCCUCCAUCUGUGGACCCGGCACCCAGUCUGCCUGCAGGCCUGGUGAUUGUGGCCCGACCUCCUGCCCACCCCUUCUGGGCACCACGGCGAUGCCCAGAGCCCCUGAGGGGCUGUGCAGGCAGGGCAUAAGAUGGCAGAGGGCUCCACAUAGCCCCUAGGCUGGCAGGAUGUGUUCUGAGCUGAGGUCCUCUGGAAAGCGCCUGUGGAUUUCUGGCCCCUCCCUGGUGUGUUCCCCACCUGCCUGCUGAGCCUUCAGAUGCCUGGGAGAGCAGGUCUCCCUUAGGUCCGCUGGUUCUGAUGGUUCCCCUCCUUCUCUCCUGGGAGCUGGGCAGGUGCUCAAAGCGGGCAGUGCAGGCUGCCCAGCGUGCCCAGCUCCCAGGAUGCACCAUGUGACCCAGGCCCCCUCCUGCCCUGCUUGCGCUGGCGAGGGGCCGUGGCUGGGUGCCCAGCGGUGCCUGCGGGGGCCCACUCCCUGGGGCAGUGCCUGCCUGCCACCCACCUGGGCUGGGCAUCCAGUCUGGCCUUGGCUGUUGUCAUGGCAGCCAAUGCCUGCAGCCGGGAGCUAAACUUGCUACCCUCAAGCCACUGUCACCACGGCUGUGACGAACAUGGGGACAUACAGCCUGGGUCGGGGAGGUGACCAGGCCUGGCUCUGCCCAGCCCCUGCUGCGGACGGUCACCGCGGUCACAGCCCACAUGGCCUGCCUGCCACCCCCUCAUGCCAUGGCCUGGGCUGUCUGAGGUUCUGUGUCAUGGAUGAGGCCCCAGGAUCACAGAAGUGCCCACAGCCACACAGACGGGCAGGAGUCGGGAGGCCCCGGCCCCCAGGCUCCCAGCCAGACUGGGGGAGUGGGGCUGGCCCAAUCUGGAGUUGCCAAGGUGGGGUUCGGUGAGGCACCAUUGUUGCUAGUGCCUGGUUUCAAAAACAUUCCAGAAAUGCCCUGCUGGCCACCUGCCUGGCUCUGAGGUCCCCACAUCUGUGGAGGAACAGGGGCUUUAAGAAGCCCUGCGGGGAAGAAGCCCCAUCCACGCAGGCUCCCCUGAGGGUUCUGAGGCACCUGCUGGGAACUGUGGUCUUCUUGGGGCGCUCGGUGUCCUCACAGCCCCUGUGGGUACCUGGCAAAGUGCCAGUGUUCCAGGGACUCAAGCGAGGCCUCUUGGAAAGGGUAAUAAUGUCCCUCAGAUCCCAGGAGAAAACCAAGGGCAGGUCCAUGAAGGACAGCCUUCCAGCGAACCCAUCCUACAGACGAGCACACUGAGGCACAGAGGACAGCCUUCCAGCGAACCCAUCCUACAGAUGAGCACACUGAGGCACAGCGAGGUUGAGGGAUGUACCCAUCACACAGCUCACAAUGGGGAGCCAGGAGGGGAACCAGGUCACACAGCCCUGUGUGAGGACAGUGGCCAUGGGCUGAGCAAUGGCCAGGCCUUGCGGGUGGAAAGGAGCUGUCCCCUCCCCUGGACCCCAGAGAACCCACCUGCCUUGGCUUUGAGCUGAGCUUUGAGCCGGGGUCACUGGCUGAGUCUCGCACCCUCUCUGAGCCUCAGGUUCCCCAUUUGUCAGAUGGGGAAGGCCAAGACCCAGGGUAGAUGGAGCCUGAGUCAGUGCUGGCAGCACUGGCGUUGUGGGCUGGCAAGGCGUGGGGCACCUCUGUGUGCAUGGGGUGGACCUGUGUGUGCCUAGCAGCCUCCCUGCCACAAACCACCCUCCUCCUGUAUGCCAGGGUCACAGGAGCUGAAGACAGUGGCCGAGCCCCGCUUUUUCUGCCCCCUCUUGAUUGUUUCAGGGACGAGGUCUGGUUCUUUGUCAACCCAAGUGCCCAGCACAAGGCUUGGCAUAUGGUGGUGGCCUGUAAAAGCCAGUGAUGUGACUAUGAAACCAAUCCACUCAUAGCACUGCACGUGCUUUUUGGGAGGGAGCUGGCUCAGAGAGGAAAGGCCAUCAGCACUGGUCCCCCCAGUAGGAUCUAGGCACCAUGGGGAACCUGCGGGCCCCUCCAGCCCCUCCACCAUGUGUCCUGGGGGUAGCCCUAUCCCCCUGGGCCUCAGUGGCGCCGUGUGCACUGGCUCUGGGGGUGCCAGGCUGCGUCUCACCAUCGGGCCAGCCCAGAAAUAGCUGUGACCUUCCGCAGCCAGCUUGGCAGCGCUUGGGGCCAAGAGGCCUACGUGCAUGCCGGCUGAGUCCCCUCACCGUGCAGGGCUGGCUAUUUUGGACGUGGCCUCCCGAGGCCAGGUCAGAGCUCUUUCCCGCGGUUCCUCAGGCCCCUCUGACGUGCGUCCACUAGAGCCUCGGCCAGUGGCCCUGGCUAGCUCCAUGAUCUCGAUCCCCCUUCCUGUCCCCGACCCCACGGGCCCUGGGUGGCACAGAGGAAGGGAUCCCAGGGACUGAGCACAGGGUGACCGCGCCUGCUGGGGCUGACAUGGAGUGUAGGGCUUGGCUGUUUUAAGAAGAAAAUGCAGAGAAAGUGCCCACCCUGGGUAGGCCCUGAAUCCUGUCUCAGCCUCUCAGAGCUCUCGCUGACUGCACAGCCUGAGCCUCGGUUUACUCAUCCACAAAAUGGGGUGAUGGGCGCCUUCCAGGACUGCUCUGAGGAUGGACAUGGGCAUUGCCUGUGCUGAGGGCACCACGCGAGGCCACUACACAGAGGGGUUCUUGGGCCUUCUCCGCCUUCCAUGGGACUGGACACUGGGUUCAGGGAGGGGCGUCAUGGGUAUAUGGGGGUGCUGCGCUGGGCAGUGGCUAAGCGUGGGCUCUUCCUUUUCUGUGACACAGCAGAGGUGUACAUGCCUGCUGCCCUGUCCAGGGCGUCUGGGUAUGGUGGAAGUGGCCCCAAGGUCCAGCCACCCUCAGGGACCACAAGCUUCCUGGACACCCUGCUGACAGGGUCCCACUGUGGAGGAACAGGCCGGCCCAGCUCCCCACCUCCCAAGUGAGCAUGGGUGGCUGGGUGGGCGUGAGGGAUUGGCUCCCCUGCUAGAGGGCAGAACUCCUGUUCCCGUGAAGGUGCUGGGUGGGGUGUGAGUCUGCUCCUGGGUUUGGGGUCAGGCAUGCCAGGAACAGCAAGCAGGGGCUGCCUGCCUGCCUAGUGCUGGCUGCAUGCUCAUGGCCCUCAGGGCCCUGUCCCCUGGAUGGUCCAGGGGUCCCGAGGAGGAGCCAUGGCCUCUUCUCCGUGGAGAGGCCCUGUGGGCCCAAGGCCUGGCUCCAUCCAGGCAGGCACAUGGAAUUCAGCCAAACUCUGGAUCCUUUCUGCAGAGCAGGCUUAGCUUGAGCCCUCCCACAGCGAGCUCGCCCACUGCCCACCCUGCCCUCUCAGCCUCUGUGACAACUCUGUGGGCACUGCCAGGGGCAGUUCCUGUGUAUUCUCAUCUGGUGAUGGGUUCAUAAUUCUCAUGUUGUGUGGGUGACUAACAAGGUCUGGGAGCUCAGGAGAGGGGCCCAGAGGCACACAGCAUGCACGGGACGGUUUUGCAGUUCCCAGGGGGCACCUGGGGUGGAGGCUUAGCCAGGCCCAGUGGGCUCAGGGCUGGCCUCAUGCCCUUCCCCUGUUGUGGACCACUUUGGGGCCUCUGGCUGAUGCUGGUGGGUGAGGACCUUCCUGGGCAGCCUCCUCCGGCCAGCAGGAGGGACCAUCAGGCCAUGCGGACCCUUGGAGAGCUUGGGGGUCGGUUCCUGCCCUGGAGUCAGCUGUGUCUGCUGAGGGUCCACUGGUGUGUGGCACAGAAGGGGUAGGGGCUGUGCCUGGUGUGCCAGGGAGGCCCUGAACUCUCCGGGAGGCCAGAUCAGGGGCCUCCUCUGGGCCUGCUGGGGGCCUCUGCAUUCUUGGCAGGGCCUCAGGGACUGGGGCGGGGAGAGGCUCCUUCUCAGAGGCUGUGAGCUCCGAAUGAAACUCCAUGCCCUCCGGGACACCAUGCCCACUUCUGGGUACUGGCCUUCAGGGGCCUUGGAUGUGGGUGGCAUGGCACUGGCUAAAUGGGGCCCAGGAGGAAGGCAGCAGGACCGUGGGCAUGCAGGCCUAAUGCCAGGGCCAGGGCAGGCUUCAUGUGGGCUUCCUCCUGUCUGGAAUCCUGGAGCCGCACAAUUUCCGACCCAACACCCCGUACUCCAGAGCGACUGGCUCUUAACGGAAGCUGCUGCUGGCAGAUGCUGUGUGCUGUGGACCCACCUGGGGUUCAUGGAGUGGGCCACGGGGCCCAGCCCUAAGCACUGCUGCGCCCAGGGUCGCCGCGCCUCCUGCUGAGGGGUCCCCGUGCCACUGGCUCUCACCAUUGCCCUCGCCUGCCGAUGGCCUCUGCUGCCCAGCCUGGGGCCAGCUCUACCGCCUGAGCCCCCUGCCCCACUCCAGGACUCACCGUACCCCGAUGGGGUAACGUGACACAGGCCCCACACGUCAGAGGCCGCUGUCCCCACGGCCACUGCCCGUGACCCCUGGCCCAAGGCAGCUGGAGUUGGUUCAGUUCAAGUUCAUUCUUCCUCUGGCCCUUGGGGGCUUGGGGCCCACCUCUGAGUGAAGGGGGCUGUCUGCCCAUCCACCAAUGUGGAGAGGGCGCCCCCGGUGUGGGGUCCAGCUCUGGACACUGCUUGGCGGCCGGGUUCACUUUGAGUUUUUAAGUUUUCUUUGCUGAGCUUUUUUGGUUGUUCUUUUUAUUUUUUGCCUCUUUAUGACUAUCCAGCUCUGAGAGACGGGAGUUUGGAGUUGCCCGCUUUACUUUGGUUGGGUUGGGGGGGGCGGCGGGCUGUUUUGUUCCUUUUCUUUUUUAAGAGUUGGGUUUUCUUUUUUAAUUAUCCAAACAGUGGGCAGCUUCCUCCCCCACACCCAAGUAUUUGCACAAUAUUUGUGCGGGGUAUGGGGGUGGGUUUUUAAAUCUCGUUUCUCUUGGACAAGCACAGGGAUCUCGUUCUCCUCAUUUUUUGGGGGUGUGUGGGGACUUCUCAGGUCGUGUCCCCAGCCUUCUCUGCAGUCCCUUCUGCCCUGCCGGGCCCGUCGGGAGGCGCCAUGGCUCGGAUGAACCGCCCGGCCCCGGUGGAGGUGAGCUACAAACACAUGCGCUUCCUCAUCACCCACAACCCCACCAACGCCACGCUCAGCACCUUCAUUGAGGACCUGAAGAAGUACGGGGCUACCACUGUGGUGCGUGUGUGUGAAGUGACCUAUGACAAAACGCCGCUGGAGAAGGAUGGCAUCACCGUUGUGGACUGGCCGUUUGACGAUGGGGCGCCCCCGCCCGGCAAGGUAGUGGAAGACUGGCUGAGCCUGGUGAAGGCCAAGUUCUGUGAGGCCCCCGGCAGCUGCGUGGCUGUGCACUGCGUGGCGGGCCUGGGCCGGGCUCCAGUCCUUGUGGCGCUGGCCCUUAUUGAGAGCGGGAUGAAGUACGAGGACGCCAUCCAGUUCAUCCGCCAGAAGCGCCGCGGAGCCAUCAACAGCAAGCAGCUCACCUACCUGGAGAAAUACCGGCCCAAACAGAGGCUGCGGUUCAAAGACCCACACACGCACAAGACCCGGUGCUGCGUUAUGUAGCUCAGGACCUUGGCUGGGCCUGGUCGUCAUGUAGGUCAGGACCUUGGCUGGACCUGGAGGCCCUGCCCAGCCCUGCUCUGCCCAGCCCAGCAGGGGCUCCAGGCCUUGGCUGGCCCCACAUCGCCUUUUCCUCCCCGACACCUCCGUGCACUUGUGUCCGAGGAGCGAGGAGCCCCUCGGGCCCUGGGUGGCCUCUGGGCCCUUUCUCCUGUCUCCGCCACUCCCUCUGGCGGCGCUGGCCGUGGCUCUGUCUCUCUGAGGUGGGUCGGGCGCCCUCUGCCCGCCCCCUCCCACACCAGCCAGGCUGGUCUCCUCUAGCCUGUUUGUUGUGGGGUGGGGGUAUAUUUUGUAACCACUGGGCCCCCAGCCCCUCUUUUGCGACCCCUUGUCCUGACCUGUUCUCGGCACCUUAAAUUAUUAGACCCCGGGGCAGUCAGGUGCUCCGGACACCCGAAGGCAAUAAAACAGGAGCCGUGGCCGUGUGUGUGGAGUGGGCUACAGCGUCAGGCGGGGCGGGCUGGUGGCCUGGGGGCCCCAGAGGCUGCUGUCUGGAUCCUGGGCUGGUGCCCAGGAUGGGGCUCCCGCGUGCUCUUGCGCUGCCCUCUGGUGGCCGCUCUGGGUCCUUGCACCCCGACCCAGGGGCCAGCCUGCCCUGUCCUGUCCUGAUACCGAGGUGGGAGCCCUGCCUUGGCCAGGGUGGCCGUGUUGACGGUUCUUGGGACUGUGACAUUGGAAGGCGAGGCAGGUCACCAGCACUGUCCUCUGCAGGAUGGGCUGGGAUUCAUUUGGCAGCUUCUCAGGGCCUGUGUCCGGCUGGUUGGUCCCUGUGCUGCCCAAACCAGGUGUCCACAUUUCCGGCUCCGAGGCGCAGAGAAGGGGGCAGGUGGUGGCUUGGGUGGAGGAAGUCACCAUCCAUCAGCCCAGGGAGGGAGGGUGCCACCUGGGCACCUGGGGCUGGAUGUGAGAGGCCUGGACCAGGGCCCGCCGGAGGGCGUGGACCAGAUGCUCAUGUGUUCCUGGGUGCAGUGUCUGUGUUGGGGGCUGGCCCCACCCUGGGCCGGGGUGCAUGGAGGGCAUGGCCCCAGCGGGGAGGAAGGUGGGCCUAGGGCUGGCUCCAGGGUGUGGAGAGCCUGGGAGUGGUCUCCGUCCUGGGGCCCCAGGAGGUUCCCGCAAGGAGCGACUGGGGCAGGUGCUGGAGGAGGUCAGUGGACAAGAUGGGGAGAUGUGGAAACCCCAAAAGCCCCUUCUCAGGCAGCCCUGCCCCCAAGACCGACAGAUGGCUAAGGGGGCCGCAGACCUGGCUCCCCCAGCUCCUGUGUGGAGAAAGGGCAACAGCUGUCCCGGAUGGUUAUUCUCUCCUUUCCUCAAACACAUUUGGAACUCAAGUAAAUCCAAUGCAUGUUGGGUGAA